GCAAAGGGUGUCGGGAGCGGCUUCCUGCAAACCUUCCCUGGCAUCUGGAGGGACCACCGUUGCCGCGUCUUCGGCUUCCACGAUCUGCGUUCGGGCUACGCGGCCACGGCGGCAGCCACUGCGACUCCCACUGUGCCUGGCUCUGUCCAUAUUAGUUCCCAGGCGGCCGUCGCCGUUCCAGCAGCGGCAGCGGCAGCGGCAGCGGCGGACAUGUUGUGAGGCGGCGGCGCGGGUGUCUGAAGGAUGGUUUGGCCGAGGCGGCGGCAACGGCUGCUGGCGGCGGCGGCAGCGGCAGCGGGGCCUCGGGCUCUAUAGAGCCGAGCCCGCUGGGUACCCGCCCGGUACCGCGGCGAGGCCAGUGCCCCUGGAUCUUGCCUCUGCUCCGACGCCGUUGGGGACCAGUUAGGCGACAGCGCCCGCCCCUCUGAGGAGACACGAAGGUGGUUCCCCAGCCGCUCAAAUUUCCGGACCACCGCGCUUUCCCCUCCUCAGCCUGGGCUGUGCUCUCUCUAGAAUCCUCGGGCCCCCACUUUCUUCCCAAACUCAUCCUAAAUCUCUCACACACGCGAGUGUUCCCAGCCCUCAAGCCAGCUGCUCCUCCGUUCAUUUUCUGCACCCUCUUCGCAAAGCACCCCCCGGGAUCACUCUCCGAGGGCGACUUUUUGAGAAAUCUCGGUGGAGUAGUGGACCAGAGCUGGGGAGUUUUUAAAAGCCGGGGCGCGAGAAACAGGAAGGUACUAUGGCUUCCUCGUCUGGCAACGAUGAUGAUCUCACUAUCCCCAGAGCUGCUAUCAAUAAAAUGAUCAAAGAGACUCUUCCUAAUGUCCGGGUGGCCAACGAUGCUCGAGAGCUGGUGGUGAACUGCUGCACUGAAUUCAUUCACCUUAUAUCUUCUGAAGCCAAUGAGAUUUGUAACAAAUCGGAAAAGAAGACCAUCUCACCAGAGCAUGUCAUACAAGCACUAGAAAGUUUGGGAUUUGGCUCUUACAUCAGUGAAGUAAAAGAAGUCUUGCAAGAGUGUAAAACAGUAGCAUUAAAAAGAAGAAAGGCCAGUUCUCGUUUGGAAAACCUUGGCAUUCCUGAAGAAGAGUUAUUGAGACAGCAACAAGAAUUAUUUGCAAAAGCUAGACAGCAACAAGCAGAAUUGGCCCAACAGGAAUGGCUUCAAAUGCAGCAAGCUGCCCAACAAGCCCAGCUUGCUGCUGCCUCAGCCAGUGCAUCUAAUCAGGCGGGAUCUUCUCAGGAUGAAGAAGAUGAUGAUGAUAUCUGAAAUUCACCAGCUGAGUUUCUAUUUCUUCUAUAAAUGUUUUUCCCUGCACAACAAAAACAGUGAAAGAAAUGCUUAUCUGUAAUUUUGUAUGCAUCUUGGUGGACUUGUCAUUGGUAUUCUAGGGAUGUCUGCUAUUAAGUUUCAUCUAUUGUGUGCUAUACAUGUAAAAACUGUCUCUUUGAACUAUUGAAAAUUUAAGGUUCAGUAUAAUAUCAAUUUUGAAUUUUUAAUGGUGUUUAUGAAAUUUUAGAUAGCAGCGAGUCCUUCGUUUGAUCAAUAAACAGUGUUACAGAUAACUUCAAGUUUAUAAAAAUACAGUGAAAUUUCUACAAAGCUCUAAAUCUGCAUUUGCAUUUCCUCUGCCCUUUUAACUAAACUAAAACUUGUGAAUUUUAAAUUAUUAAGGGGGGGGUGCUGUGUGAAUCAGUAGACAUUGGAUUGGGUUGGUGAAAGAGUUCAGUUCUGUAGUAUCUGAAUUUGUCUUUUAAAAUGAGUACAUAUAUAGGCAAUAAAUAUAUAUGCUCAGAUCAAUAUACUUGUUUAGAAAAACUUCAAGACAUUCAAAAACUAGGAAGGAGUAUGUUUAAUAGUAUUUGUAUAAAUUUGGUGGUUAUGUUUUUUUAUUUUGUUUCUGUUUUGUGUAGAGGUAAAAACUAUAGUUUUAUUACAGCAUAAUUCAUUUUGAGCUCCACUAUGACAUUUCAAAGACUGCCCAGUUUGGAAGUCUGUCAUGAUUUUUACUCUUUCACUCCAAUUCAGUAAUUGUUGAUAGUAUUACUUACCUAGUCCAUCCAUACUCAUAUUAUUCAAAUAUAUAGGUGGUACUUUUGAAACAAUUACAUUGGUUCUCUUGGUUUAACUGAGGUUUAUGAAUAUUCAAACCUUUGCUGGGGGAAAGAAAUGAAAGUUAAUGAGCAUGCUUGCUAUGAGAGAGGGAUUUUUAAUUUAACUUGUAGUUAUAGUUUACUUAUUGUUUUUAGAAUUACUUUUACAUUUUCCCAACUAGAUGGCCUAGAGUCCAACAUUACCUUUUGAGAUGACAUUAUUGUCUCCAUAAUUGAGUGAUAGCUUUAAAAAAAAGAUUAGUUUUGCUUAAGAAGUUAUGUUACAACUGAUCAGCCCUAUAUGAAUUAACUGAUCAGCCCUAUAUGAAACAUAAGUUGUGUUAUAACUUAUCAGCCGUAUAUGGAACAUAAAUAGUUUCUACCUGCUUGUUAGAGAAGCUUUAAUUUGGUUCUAAUAAAUACAGUAUGGUAGUGUUUAUAGGAAUCCAGGAUGUUGAAGAAAUGGCAUAAUGUCUAUAUUUUGGAAACAGAAAGGAAAAGUCACUUAAGAUAGUAUUAAGUAAUUAAAUUCCUAUGUCAGUUGCCAAAUCUUUUAAACUUAUGUAUUCACCAAGCCCAAAAAUAGAUUGUGGCUCCCAGGAUUCCAAUUUUAAUUGGAGAGCUAAGUAAGUAAAGUUUUAUAACUGUUAGGUUUCUUAAUGAUCAUAUUUUGCAGUUUUAGUAAAAGGGAAAUAUUGUUAUACAUUUAUUAAAUAUACUUCCCCCAUGAAGUGAAAAGGUUAAUUUUGCUGAAUGUUUUAAGUUGAAGUUACUUCAUGGAUGUCAUACCCAUGAAGUGCAUUUGGAUGAGAUAGAAGAAAUUGUUUUUUAAAAAGUUUAAGUACCAAAGGUAGUCUAGUCUAGAACGAUAAGUUAAUACGUGUUGGCUUUUCUAAUUUGUACUGUAACAUCCUUAUACUUUCUAUUUUAAGUAUAUCUGUUUCUUAAGUAAACAACUUAGAUAUUUUCCACACCUUUUUUUUUUUUUCUGAUGCAGAGUUCAGGUUAAUAUUUUACUGCAUCUGAUAAUGUAUUAUACGUUUGAAGCCUAGUGACUUUUCAUUUUGACAUUCUUGUGAUUUCAUAUGCUGUAUUCUUCAAGCAAUAAAAUUGUGAUGUGUUUUAUAAAUGGUUUUUAUAUUUAAUGUUCUAUAGAGAGAUUUCUAUUAUUACCAUUUUUACUAUUUUCAAGAAUCUUAGGCCCAAAAGACAUUUUGGUCAUUUGGUAUGUAGUACCUGCCUUUUGUUUUUGUUUACUGUUAUUUCAAAAAAUGUGGUUUUACUUGUAUUUUUAUAAUUUACAGUCCUAAGAUCGAGGCAUAACAAAGCUUACUUAUGCAAUAUUUUAUUUUUAGGUUUUUUCUUUUUUUUUUUUUUUUUUUUUUUUUUUUAGCAUUUAAGAGUCACUAUUAUGUUUUGCCAGUUAAAAUUUUUUAAAUCUUUUGAAGAGAGAAACAAAAUCUUCAGCGUUCUUGAGAAAUAAAAUUAUUGUUCAGUAAGUAUUUUUCCAUCCCCUUGAAUAUAUGUUAUAUAUUCUUUUUCGGCAGAUUAUCAGAUUAGUAAGUGUUUAAAAGGCAUCAGUUUUUAAAACUGCAUAUACCACACACACACAAAACAGUACACAAAUAAAGGUUUUCACAAAUUAAACAAACUCACAUACUAGUCUUCAGAUCAAAACACAGAGCAUUAUGUGUACCCCAGAAGCCCUCCUCUUUCCCCAUCUUAACACUGUCUUCUUUCUUGCUGAAAGUUACUAUCCUGACUUCUAAAAUCAUAGAUUAGUUUUGCCUGUUUUUUAUUUUAUGUAAAUGUAAUCAUACAUAAUACACUUUUUUUCAUUCAUCAUUUUUGUGAAUAUUUUAGUUUCUUGUUGCCACUGUAACAAACUACCACAAACUUAGUGACUUAAAACAACACAGAUUUAUUCUUUUAUAGUCCUGGAGAUCAGAAGUCCAAAAAUCAGUUUCAUUAGGCCUAAAUCAAAGUAUCAGCAGGGUUGGCUCUUUAUUGAGGUUGUGAGGGAGAAUGUUUUCUUCCCUUUUUUGGCUUCCAGUGACGGCCUGUAUUUAUGGGCUUGUGACCCCUUCCUCUCUAUGAUCAAAGCUUGCUUUUGUCAUUAUAUCAUCUUCUCUUCUGUAGUCAGAUCUUUCCCUGCCUCUAAGUUUAGGGCUCACCUGCAUAAAGCAGGGAUAAUCCCCCUAUCUCAAGAUCCUUAAUUUAAUCACAUCUGCAGAAUCUCUUUUGCCAUAUAAGUGACAUUCACAGGUUCCAGGGAUUCAUACGCUGGCUAUCUUUGGAGGCCGUUAUUCAACCUGCCAAAGUGAGAUCCAUUCUUAUUGUUGCAUGUAUUUGUAGUUCAUUCAUUCUCAUUGCUGUAUAGUCUUCCGUUUGUUUAUCCAUUUUUCAUUACAUCCAAAAGUUAUUCAUUCUCCCAUUAAUAGUCUUUUGAGAAUUUUUCAAUUCUGAGCUAUUAUGAAUAGUACUGUGUAGAACAUUCUUAUACAUGUCUUUUGGUGAGUGUAUACAUUUCCAUUGAGUAUAAACCUAAGAAUGGAAUUGCCAGGUUGUAGGGUGUGUAUAUUUUCAGUUUUAGUAUUUACUGUCAAACAGUUUUCCAAAGUGACUGUAAGAAGGCACCAUUUUAAUGUGUAGCAUAAAAAUGAAUUACGCUAAUGAUCUUAGUGGGUUGAAUUUCUCGAAACACCUAAAUUGUACCAAAUGAGUUAUAUUGCAGCAGGUAUGUUGUUAAUUUCAUAUAACAGGAAAAUAAGAGCAAAAGUAAUUGCCCUUAUUAACUGACACAUUAGUAUUACAUACUCAUUAGGUUAUUGCUCCUUAGAAAAAAUGCAAAUUUUAAGUAAUCGUAAGUAGUAUGUUGAAUUAGUAUGUUGUGGGAAAAUCUGUGAUUUAAUUUUUUAAUUGAAUUUUAAAUUUUGGGUUAUAACCUCAUUAAAAUGCAUGAUAUUUCCUUAUAUAGGUUUCUAAAUUAUGUCUGUCCAACUCAUCUAUAUCCAAAUGGCCAUUAGGAAGAAUUAUCCAAUUCAGAUGGCAUAGGCACUGCCUUCCAAUUUCUUCAUUUGUAUUUUUUUGUUGCUGUUUUCUUUUUUGCCUCUGUCCCCAACAAUUUGACCACAAGUCCUACCCCACCUCCUCUGUUUUUCACCAUCCCCCAGGAUAUAAAGUGUCAUGGUUAGGAUCGGCCAGGGUGAAGAGAAUGAUAACAUAAGUAGCCUCCUUUCACCUAAAGUAUUACCACUGGUUCUUAUCCUAUUUCCUCAAAAUAAAUGAGAAGAGAAAGUAAGGAAUAAGAGGAAGAAACUUUUUUUUUUUUUUUAAAGAAACAGGGUCUCACUAUGUUUCCUUUUUCUUUUUUCUUUUCUUUUCUUUCUUUUUUUUUUUUUUUUUUUUGAGACAGAGUCUUGCUCUGUCACCCAGGCUGGAAUGCAGUGGCGCGAUCUCGGCUCACUGCAAGCUCCGCCUCCCGGGUUCACGCCAUUCUCCUGCCUCAGCCUCCUGAGUAGCUGGGACUACAGGUGCCCGCUAGCACGCCCAGCUAAUUUUUUUUGUUUUUUUUUAGUAGAGACAGGGUUUCACCGUGUUAGCCAGGAUGGUCUCGAUCUCCUGACCUCGUGAUCCACCCGCCUUGGCCUCCCAAAGUGCUGGGAUUACAGGCGUGAGCCACUGCGCCCGGCCUAUGUUUCUUAAUAUAGAUUGCAGUGGCUAGAUUACAGUGACUAUUCACAGGCAUAAUCAUAAUGCACCAUAGCCUCAAACUCCUGGGCUCAAGCAAUCCAAAAGGAGGAAACUUUUAACUUAUGAUCAGUUUCUACCAUAAAUCAAGCAACUUAGAAAAACCUUAGAACAGGGUUUCUCAAACCAAGCAUUGUUAGUAUUUGGGGUUGGUUAAGUCUUUGUUUGUGGGAGCCUAUCCUGUGCAUUGUAGGAUUUCUAGCAGCAUAAUUGGCUUAUGCCCACUUGAUGUCAUUAGCACCACUCCCCACCCUACUUCCAGUUGUGACAACCCAAAAAUGUCUCCAGACAUAGCCAACUGUCCCUGGGUGUUGCGAGUAUAGGAGGCAAAAUUGCACCCUGUUGAAAACCACCACCUUAGAUCAUCUAGGUUUUACUUUUAGGAUAAGACACUUGAGGGAAAGGCUGUGAAACUGAACCUCUGUUAGAAGCAACACACAGUAUCACUGCAAAAAGACUAAAAGAAAUAGGUGAUUUGGAAAGAGGAGGCCCAGGAUUAAAAUAUGUUUCCAAGAAAGUCAAAUCUUACAGGAGACUCUUGACUUCACAUCUGCUGAUCCCUUUACCCGAUAGGACCUAGAGCAGCCAUUAUAAAUCUCUGUACCUGCUUGCUGCUUUUCUACCUCAUUGUUAGCCACACCCAGUUUGAAACAGAUGAGGUAUGCUAUUUCAUAACUAGUACAUCUUUUAAUAAGCAUUUUUUAUUGUGAUUAAAUAUGCAUAUCGUAAAAUUCACCACUUUAACCAGUUUUAAGUGUUCAAUUCUGUGGCAUUAAGUAUAUUCAUACUAUUGUGCAACCACCACCACCAUCCGUCUACAGAACUCUUCAUCUUCCCAAACUGAAAUUAUGUAUUCAUUAAACAAUAACCACCCAUUACCUCCUCUCUCCUCAGCCUCUGGUAACCAGCAUUCAGUCUCUAUGAAUUGACUACUCUGGAUAUCUAAAUGGAUUCAUUCUUAUUUCAUUUACCAUAAUGUCUUCAAAGUUCAUUCAUGUUGUAGCAUGUAUUAGAAUUUCUUUCCUCUUAAAGGCCAAAUAUGCCGUAGUAUGUAAAUACCGUAUUUUGUUUAUCAGUUCAUCCAUUAAUGGACACUGGGUUGCUUCUGCUUUUUGGCUAUUGUGAAUAAUGCUUCUGUGAACGUGGGUAUACAAAUAACUGUUUGAGUCCUAAUAGGCUUGUUAUUUUUGAGUGCACAGAUCUGUAUAUUCGCAAUUGAAAUAGGGAAAGUCUUUAUAUUCAUAUAAAGAUAAUUUAUAAUACAAUAAGUCCUCAAUGUUGUUGAUAGGUUCUGGGAAACUGCGAGUUUAAGAAAAACAACAUAUAAUGAAAUCAAUUUUACCAUAGGUGAACUGAUAUAAAUAAGAGUUAAGUCCCUAUGGCAUAUAUUUCUGGUUACAAAAACACUACCAAAUUUCUAAUAAAGACCCAAAACACUUCUAAAAUUAAACAUUGAGAUUAAUAUGAGCUUUAUAUACAUUUAAAAAGGAUAAAAACAAGUAAGAAUUGGCUGGACAUGGUGGCUUACGCCUGUAAUCUCAACACUGGGAAGUCGAGGUGGGCAGAUGGCUUGACCUCAGGAGUUCGGAACCAGCCUGGGUAAUAUGGUGAAACCCGUCUCUACAGAAAAAUUCAAAAAUUAGCCAGAGGUGGUGGCUUGCACCUGUAGUCCCAGCUACUCGGGAGCCUGAUGUGGGAGGAUCCCUUGAGCCUGGGAGGUCGAGGCUGCAGUGAGCCAUGAUCACGCUACUGCACUCCAGUCUGGGCAACAGAGCAAAAUCCUAUCUCAAAAAAAAUAUAUAUAUUAUCCAGCCCCAAAUGUUUAUGGGGUUGUUAUUGAUAAACCCUGCAUUAAACAAUCCCACAGUCGGUGCUGCGGUGAGCCGUGAUGGUACCACUGCAUUCCAGCCUGGGUGACAGAAUGAGACCCUGUCUCAAAAAAAAAAAAAAAAAGUAAAAAUUAUUUACCCAAUAUUUGGCGAAUCAGUGAGUGACAGCAGUUGUAGUGCUAGUGGGUUAAAUCAAGGAAUAACUGUUGGGAAGUGAAAAUUUUAAGGAGCACCUCCUACCACCAUGCAGUUCAAAAACAAAAAAUAAGAAAUAAAGUGGGCUUGCUGAGUGCUUUCAUACUGCAUCAUUUAUUGUGCAUUUGUAUGAUUAUUAUAUACUUUACAAAUUUUCGUUUUACAGUAAUUUGUAUUCAUUCGUUUUUCAACCUGCUUAUUUCAGUUCAGUGUCUUGGGUAGCUGGAGCCUAUCCCAGCAGCUCAGGGAGCAAAGUGGGAGCCAACCCUGGACAGGAUGCCUUUUCAUCACAGGGCGCACUCACACGGCACACACACGCAUACUGGGACCAUUUAGCUGUACCAAUUCACCUAACGUGCAUCUUUGGGAAUUGAGAAGAAACCAGAAUACCCAGAGAAAACUCAUGCAGAUAUGUGGAGGACAUGCAAAAUUCACACAGACAGUGGCCCUGGUUGUAAAUAAUUGUUUUUCAUCAAUGUUAUAAUGAAAUUACAGGCCGGGUGUGGUGGCUUACGCCUGUAAUCCCAGCACUUUGGGAGGCCGAGGCGGGUGGAUCACGAGGUCAGGAGAUAGAGACCAUCCCGGCCAACAUAGUGAAACCUCAUCUGUGCUAAAAUACAAAAAAUUAGCCAGGCUUGGUGGUGUGCACCUGUAGUCCCAGCUACUUGGGAGGCUGAGGCAGGGGAUUUCUUGAACCCAGAAGGCGGAGGUUGCAGUGAGUUGAGAUCGCGACACUGCACUCCAGCCUGACAACAGAGCAAGACUUCGUCUCAAAAAAACAAACAAAAAAAGAAAUUACAUUAGUUGAGGACCUGCUGUAUGUGAUAUGAACAAUGAGGAUCAACUCUUUUUGUAAUAGUUUUUUUACAUAUGUUAUUUCAUUUGUUUAUUUCCUCUGUGAGGGUAAGUAUUGAUAGUCCAGUCAUAGACUGGUAACACAGGCACACCAUUAAAAAUAAUAGACAUACAGUAUGCAGUAUUUUGUUUUACUUAUGAAACUCCGUAUUUUAUGUAUGAUGUAUUGAGUAUGAAGAAUAGUACAUACUGUUUCCUUUUAACUUUAUGUUUCUUGCCUUUGUAUAUUUUAUAUGAAUAGCACUUGUCACUAACAUAGAAAGCAGUAGAGGUGGAAGAGGGAGACUUGCCAGAAUAAGUUUUUAAUGUGAAUCAGAGAUUUUUAUUAGGAAUUGGGAGUGGAAGGAGAGAGAUAGUAUUAGAAAGUAUGUAUGCAGCAAAGGAUGGAGAAACUGUCCUUGUUGUUAAGGCAUCUAAGGAUGCUCCAAUUACUGGGGAAAACAUACCAGGCUCAAAAUGGUCUGAUUAUGCAAAUACCUUCUAAUACGUUUGUUUCUUUUGUUGUGCCUAUAAAAGAUGCCAUUAACUUCAUAUUUAUGUCACUAAUAAACUUCUAGAAUCCAUGUAGUAGGGUGUAGUAGUGUGGUUAAGCUAUGAAGAACAAUGGUAUUUAUUUCCAAAACACUUAUUUGGUAUAUUACAUAGGAUAGAGUAUGUUUUCUAAGCCAAAUAGUGUUAGGUUUUCAUGUGCAGUUGCCUUACACAUAUACUAGUAGCCCUUACAAAAUUUCGUCUGUCUUUAUUAUAAACAUGUUGUAAGUGAGGAAACUAAGAUUCCAAGAAAUUAAGUACUGUUGGCCCUCUGUGUCUGGGGGUUCCACAUCUAUAGAUCGACCAACCAUGGACUGAUGGAUUGAAAACAUUUGGGGAAAAAACAAAAAAUAACCCAACAAUGAAAUAGUAUAAAUUUUAAAAAUAAUAUAACAAUAUUUAUAUAUCAUUUACAUUAUGUUAGAUAUUAUAAUCUAGAGAUGAUUAGCAUCCUUGGAUUUUGGAUUUUGGUAUCCUUGGGGUAUCCUGGAACCAAUCCCUGGCGGAUACCAAGGGAUGACUGUAAUAUAAUAACAUCUAACAAGUGAAGGAUUUGAACCCCAAUGUAAGUAAUUAUGAAAACUAUUUUUCUUCCACUAGAACUUUUUUCCCCAAAAAUACUCUGGAAAUACUGGAACAAAUACUAAAAUAAAUGACCUUUAUUUGAAGAUCUUUUAAAAAAAUUAUAAGCCUGCCUGAGGAUAGCAAAAUUGUGUGCUUUUGCAAGGUAAUUGUAGAACUCAUUCUAAGGAAGCAGAGGUAAUGUCUGUUACUAUUUUCAGCUCCCUUUUUCUGUCCACUGUUGUCUAAAUGAUUCACUCAGUGUUAUGCAGAAUAUGAGAAGUUAUUUUAUAAAGUUGAUUUGUGGUA